GAAGACUCAUUUUUGUCUUCAUUACUGCUAUGUGGAGCAAGGGCCCAAGCUUUUAAAAACAAGAGCUCAGAGACAUGGCCCUGGCCUUGGAAGAUGCCCUAGAGACGCUGAGGUGGUUGUACUUUUGCCAUAGGAGUGGCAGCCAGAGAACUGAGCCCAAUGAAUGCAAAGGCUGGUGCCUGGAAAUAUUGUGACUUUGCCACAGAAAGAAGAUGGAGAAUUUUAAAGUUGGAAAUCUGCCUGGUAAGGGAUCAUUUGCUGGUGUCUGCAAAGUUGAGUCCAUACACACUGGUUUGGAAAUUUCAGUCCAGAUGAUAGUUAAGAAAGCAGUAAGAAUACAGAGAGUCCACAAUGAGAUGAAAAUGCACUGCCAGUUGAAACAUCCUCCUACACUGGAGCUUUAUAAAUAUUUUAAAGACAAGGAUUGGAUUAGAUUUGACAUUAGAAAUGUACCAUAAUACAGAAGGCAAUGGACACCUAAAGAACAGAAUGAAAACCUUCUUAGGAAAUGAAGCUUGACACUUCACCCACCAGGCCACCACAAGAAUGUUGCAUUUUCAUUAUUAUGAUACUUCAAACAAAAUAAUGGAGCCCCACAGACCGAAUGUGAAGACAGCAGUGCCAUUGUCUUUGGAAAGCUAUCACAUAUCUGAAGAGUAUGGCUUUCUUCUUCCAGAUUCUCUGAAAGAACUUCCAGAUCAUUAUAGGCCUUGGAUGGAAAUUGCCAACAAACUUCCUCAAUUGAUUGAUGCUCACCAGCUUCAAGCUCAUGUGGACAAGAUGCCCCUGCUGAGCUGCCAGUUCCUGAAGGGUCACCGGGAGCAGCGCCUGGCCCACCUGGUCCUGAGCUUCCUCACCAUGGGUUAUGUCUGGCAGGAAGGAGAGGCGCAGCCUGCAGAGGUCCUGCCAAGGAAUCUUGCCCUUCCAUUUGUCGAAGUCUCCAGGAACUUGGGGCUCCCUCCUAUCCUGGUCCACUCAGACUUGGUGCUGACGAACUGGACCAAAAAAGAUCCAGACGGAUUCCUGGAAAUUGGGAACCUGGAGACCAUCAUCUCAUUUCCUGGGGGAGAGAGCCUGCAUGGUUUUAUACUGGUGACUGCUUUGGUAGAGAAAGAAGCAGUGCCUGGGAUAAAGGCUCUUGUUCAGGCCACGAAUGCUAUCUUGCAGCCCAACCAGGAGGCCCUGCUCCAAGCCCUGCAGCGACUGAGACUGUCUAUUCAGGACAUCACCAAAACCUUAGGACAGAUGCAUGAUUAUGUAGAUCCAGACAUAUUUUAUGCAGGCAUCCGGAUCUUUCUCUCUGGAUGGAAAGACAACCCAGCAAUGCCUGCAGGGCUGAUGUAUGAAGGAGUUUCCCAAGAGCCCCUGAAAUACUCCGGCGGGAGUGCAGCUCAGAGCACAGUGCUUCAUGCCUUUGAUGAGUUCUUAGGCAUUCGUCAUAGCAAGGAAAGUGGUGACUUUCUGUACAGAAUGAGGGAUUACAUGCCUCCUUCCCAUAAGGCCUUCAUAGAAGACAUCCACUCAGCACCUUCCCUGAGGGACUACAUCCUGUCAUCUGGACAGGACCACUUGCUGACAGCUUAUAACCAGUGUGUGCAGGCCCUGGCAGAGCUGCGGAGCUAUCACAUCACCAUGGUCACCAAAUACCUCAUCACAGCUGCAGCCAAGGCAAAGCAUGGGAAGCCAAACCAUCUCCCAGGGCCUCCUCAGGCUUUAAAAGACAGGGGCACAGGUGGAACCGCAGUUAUGAGCUUUCUUAAGAGUGUCAGGGAUAAGACCUUGGAGUCAAUCCUUCACCCACGUGGUUAGGAGGCUGCCCUCUCCCCAGCAAUGCAGAGCCCCCAUGGAGGGCAGGUGGGCCUGGAGAAUGAGGGUCAGGGUUCUGCCUGGGAUCAUCCAGGAAGGAUCUCAGCCCUAUUCAUGUUUCUGCUCUACAGAGCACUAUAUUCUCCUUGUUGAGAGCUGUUGGCUUCACAAAGGAGAGUUGAUGUGGCCAAGCCUUUCCCUCCCUACCUGAUCACUGCUUAACGGCAUGUAUAAUGGAUACUUCCUCAUGCAGAACCCCCAGAGGAGUGACUGUAUGCCAUUCUCUUUGCCAAGUAAUAGAAAACCAAUCUAAAUGUCAAAAAUCAGAUAAAAUUGCCUGGGGAUACAUUACUUGUUGAUUUUCUUAAAAAACAAAUUCACUUAACAAUUCAUUAAGUUCAUACUGAGCACUGCCUCCAAGAUUAAAACCAGGAUUUCUGUGGUCCCAGACCAGCCCUCUUCUCCCUGAAUGUGUUGAGUUGGUGGCAGGAGGUUGGAAAUGCUCCAGUGGAGAUGGGAAGAUAGAGGAUGCUGACAAUAAGGACUUGGAAGUCACUAGUGUGAAAAUGAGCAGUUAAUGAUAUGGGAACGGAUGAGACUUUCCACGUGGUACCUAGAUUUGCAAAUUCUAUUGUAAUGCCUUUAUUUUUAGAAGAAUUAUUCUCUCUUCUUACUCUGAAAAUCUGUAUUUGUAAAAUGAAUGAAUGGAUCCUAUAUAAGUAAAUAAGAAAACUGGGAAUAAGUAGUAAAUCAAUGUGUUUAGUGUGCAAAUAAAUGUAAAUGCUUUUAUUGA